GAGAGGAAGGCGCUCGGUUACAUUGGAGAACUGGAGUGGUCUGGAGUUCCACGGUGUAGUGGACCAGAGGCCACCUCUCCUGGGCUUCUCAGUGUCUCGCCGGCGGGGUUCGGCCUGAGCUGGAUAGACAUAGCCCUUGGCGGAUUUAAACAACCUAAACAUUAAGCAAUACAGCUGCCUCAAACCUUUGGGAUUUUCAGAAUGACUGACACUGCCGAAGCUGUUCCAAAUUUUGAAGAGAUGUUUGCUAGUAGAUUCACAGAAAAUGACAAGGAGUAUCAGGAAUACCUGAAACGCCCUCCUGAGUCUCCUCCAAUUGUUGAGGAAUGGAAUAGCAGAGCUGGUGGGAACCAAAGAAACAGAGGCAAUCGGUUGCAAGACAACAGACAGUUCAGAGGCAGGGACAACAGAUGGGGGUGGCCAAGUGACAAUCGAUCCAAUCAGUGGCAUGGACGAUCCUGGGGUAACAACUACCCGCAACACAGACAAGAACCUUACUAUCCCCAGCAAUAUGGACAUUAUGGUUACAACCAGCGGCCUCCUUACGGUUACUACUGAUAGAAAUGUUGGCAGCUUUUAGUAAAAGCAUUUACUCUGUUACCAUGAGAAAAGUUUGGGUGUCUUCUGUUGGUCAUAGUUUUACAUCUGAUUUUACAGAAUGGAUUAUUGAUUUUUUGGAAGUUGAGACUUUAAAAAAAAUAGAUCUUACUUGCGAAAUGCGAUGGUUGCUGGGAAUACCUGAAACUGUGGAUUAUAUUGCUUGACUUCUACCUCAGAAUCUUCUUUGUUUCAUGACUUAAUAGUGCUUUAAGUUUGGUAUAUUAUUUGACCUCUAGGAAUUCUUUGUUUUACACAGAAAUAAAAAUUUUAAAAUAGAAAAUGCUUUUACUUUGUAAGGUAAGAGAGUAUCCAUAUGCUUAGAUGUGCUCGUUUCUAAAAUUCUAGAGGUUGAUAUAAUCAGCUCAUGAAUGCACAGCUAUGCUUUUUGUGAUAGAUUGUACAUAACAUCAGCAGUUGAAAGGUAAAACAAUUGCUUUUUUUUUUUUUUGCAUUUGUUAAGUGACUAUGGUACUUUGUGAUUCCUUAAUCUAUAGAUGAGUCAGCUCCACACUUGAGUCUCUUUUUAGAGGGAAAUCAGUAAUAAAGCUGUAAAAUAAGGAAAAAAAAAAAAAAAAAAAAAGACUUGUUUGAUGUCAUGUUUGAGAUUUUCUCUUUAACCUUAAAAGAUCAGCCUGGACAAUUGCACACAAUUAUAAGUAAAUGUGAAAAUUAGGUUCUGUAAUUAGGAUGGCAGUAAACAUAGUGGAGAACCAUAACUAAUCAAUACAGACAUGUCAGCAAUCCUCGAUUCCUUAAUCUUCAAGAGAAAAAAAGUCAUAAUGAAGAAGCUAAAGUUGCUGAAGAUGUGAGACUGAAAGUCCAUCCCAGCGAGGACGGCUUCGUUUCCCAGCCCCGAGUCACUCACUACCUCUUUUUCACGUAGCCAGAGCUGCAUCUUUUUUCAUGUAUUUCAGGGCAUUCUGGCUAGAAGGAAAAAUGUGUUACUUAUGAUCUUCUUUUGAAACUCGAGCUUCCUGCACCCCACAUCGUUGUAGCAACAUCGUCACCACACGUGUGCUCAGCACUCAGAGGUGCAAAGAUGACCAAGAAGCUCUCGGGUUUUCUCACACUAGUUGCUACAGCAGAAAUCUGCUGUGUGUUUUGAGACAUCUUGGGAAUGACACACCAAUGUGCCACCCCCUCGGGAUCUUAAAAUAGGUCCAGAUUGAAUCUUUAGCUAAUGUUGUUAUUGUAAACCCUGAGUUCCACCAAAUGUUUCUGAGUUUCUGGACCAAUAUUGCAUUUCAAAUAGAUCAAUCAUGGUCUCUCCAUGAGAAAUGAAUUCUAUUGGAACGCUUUCUGAGCUCACAGCUCCUCAACGUAUUUACUGAAAACUUGGCAUGACAGCGUAGCUCCUUUGUUUCCGUUAAAAAUUUCAGUUAAAAUUACUAUAAAAUAAAGUGCAAAAGAUCACAAUCACAGAUAGAAAUGACCAGAUUGGGGUAUACUGAGUUUCCUUAACAUCUGGAGAGCUGCUGAGUAUCCCCAGAAUGCCCAGGCAUUUUUCAUUUAUUAAUUGUGAUGUCAUGACAUAACUGGCCUAAUAGAGCUAUAAAAAGUGUUGUAAGAUGUAAAUGUUGACAUUUAGAGUGUCCCUGUCAUCACUGAGUAUGGUCAUGCUGUUACUACAAAUAAGGGAUGGAAUGUUAAUGGACUCAAUUGUAUCCCUCCAUGUUCACAUUUGGAAGCUCCAACCCCCAGUGUGAUUCUAUGUGGAGAAAGGGCCUGUAAGGAAGUAAUGAAGGUGAAGUGAGGUCCUAAGCCUGGGGCCCUGAUUCGAUGGGAGUAGUGUCCUCAGAGGAAGAGGAAGAGAGACCAGAGCUCUUGCUCCACCACGAAAGGGCGCUGCAAGAAGCAGCUGCCUGUGAGCCAGGAAUUGGGCCCUCACCAGGACCAAAUGGCUGGCACCUUGGUCUUGGACUUCCAGCUUCCAGAACUAUGGGAAAUAAAUGUCUGUUUUGUAAGCCACCCAAUCCAUAGUACUUUGUUAUGGCAGCUCAGGCAGACUAAGAAAGGAGCAAAACACACCAAGGCAUUUUAAAUUUAUUAACCUUGUUUCGUUGCACACCUGGCCUACCAGAGCUAUAAAAUACAUUUUAAGAUGCGCCUUUUUGUUGACCCUUAGAGGGUCACUAUCACUAUGGGGUAAGGUGAUGAAAUUACUUGAGCUAAAGCAACUGUGUUGACUGUGUUUUGCUCUAACCUAUGUUACCAUUAGAUAGAACCCAUGGAAGUAAAAUGCUGUAGAAAAACGUGAGAACCAGCCAGUUUGCACAUUUCUUCCUGUGGCAUAGUACUUCCUUUGGCGUGAUGCCUCCUGGACUGAAACAAGCCAAGUGAGAUACGUCUUCUGCCAUCCAGAGGAGAAAGCCACAGUCUUGUGAGUCUUGUCUCUUUUGGCCAUUGGCGCUUUAAUAAGCACUCAGGAAUUCAGUGGGCUUAGCUUCGGUUUUUAAUGACAAACUGUCACGUGAAGACAUUUAUCAGGAGCGUCUCUCCUUUGUCACCUCUGGACAGUGGGUGGGGAACCCUGGUGUAGACAUGACUUCCGCAGUGUUUCAGCACGGCCUGGCCAGAGCUCAGAGAAGGUGCGCAGGAUGCUUAAGCUCUCCACCACCAGCUGCUUCUUCCCAUUGGUUUUCGCCUCUGUGCUUUGAAGUUGCUCAACAAUUUAAUCACCAAGACUCACAGGAGGCAAAGUGGAGGGAGCCGUUUCCGCAGAUCACAGCGACAGUGCUGUGGUUUGCCCCAAGAAGGCCGUGAUCUCUGGUGCAAGUCCUACAGGGUGCAGAGUGCUAGACCCUAGGGUGAGCUGGACAUCAGGGCCUUGGAUGAGGCAGUGUGCUUUCUAAACAAGCAAGAAUUCAGCACUUUUAGCUCACAAGUAGCAAUUUGGUUGUUUCUAGGAUCUAAUUAUGUGUAAUAUGAUACCUUGAAAAGUAUGCGAAUGCGAGUAAAACUUACCAAACUGCUUUGUCUUUAUUAGAAUUGAUAUUGAAAUAAUUAUCGUGUAUAUGCUUCAAGUCUGUUUAUCCCAAGUGAAUUAUGAAUAAAAGCAGUCAACGACCAA